AGUCCUUAGUUACAAGGCUCCAUCCUCACUUUGUUCGCUCCUCAGUCGUCCAGGCGGAUUCCUUUUUCGCCAGGCACCAAGGCACAGCUUAGAGUAGACCCGAGUCCUGCUCUGCGGAGUUCGUCUUCCCAGCGAAGGUACAGAGGCGGAUGAACUGCUGAGACUUGGGUCUCACUCUGUCGCCCGGUACAGUGGCGUGAUCUUGGCUCACUGCAACCUCCACCUCCCAGGUUCAAGUGAUUCUUAUACCUCAGCCUCCUGAGUAGCUGGGACUACAGAUUGACGUAUUUUAAGAUUUUUUUAACUUCUGAAGUCUAGCAGGCCUGUAAGAACAAAAAUCAUUCUGUAGGAAUUAAAAACAGAAUCCAGUCUUGACAACAUAUCCACAAUGUCUGAUGUAUCUACUAGUGUACAAUCAAAAUUUGCUAGACUUGCAAAGAAAAAGGAAAAUAUCACCUAUAUGAAAAGAGAGCAGUUAACAGAAACUGAUAAGGACAUAGCUCCGGUAUUAGAUUUAAAAUGCAAGGACGUAUCAGCAAUUAUGAAUAAGUUUAAGGUCUUAAUGGAAAUUCAAGACCUGAUGUUUGAGGAGAUGAGGGAAACUCUUAAAAAUGACCUAAAAGCAGUUUUAGGGGGAAAAGCUACAAUACCUGAGGUAAAGAAUUCAGAGAACUCCAGUAGUAGGACAGAGUUUCAGCAAAUAAUCAAUUUAGCAUUACAAAAAACAGGGAUGGUAGGGAAAAUAGAAGGAGAAAACUCUAAAAUAGGUGAUGAUAAUGAAAAUUUAACCUUUAAAUUAGAAGUAAAUGAGCUGAGUGGUAAAUUAGACAACACUAACGAAUACAAUAGUAAUGAUGGUAAGAAAUUACCCCAGGGUGAAUCACGAAGUUACGAAGUCAUGGGAAGUAUGGAAGAAACCUUAUGCAAUAUAGAUGACAGAGAUGGAAAUCGCAAUGUCCAUUUAGAAUUUACAGAAAGAGAGAGUAGGAAGGAUGGAGAGGAUGAAUUUGUCAAAGAAAUGAGAGAGGAAAGAAAAUUUCAGAAAUUGAAGAAUAAAGAGGAGGUUUUAAAAGCCUCCAGAGAAGAAAAAGUGUUGAUGGAUGAAGGAGCAGUACUUACCCUGGUAGCCGACCUUUCAUCAGCAACACUGGAUAUUAGUAAGCAAUGGAGUAAUGUCUUCAACAUUCUGAGAGAAAAUGAUUUUGAACCUAAAUUUCUGUGUGAAGUUAAAUUAGCAUUUAAAUGUGAUGGUGAAAUAAAGACAUUUUCAGAUCUGCAAAGCCUUAGAAAAUUUGCCAGCCAAAAAUCUUCUGUGAAAGAAUUACUGAAAGAUGUACUCCCACAAAAGGAAGAAAUAAAUCAAGGAGGAAGAAAAUAUGGAAUUCAAGAAAAAAGGGAUAAAACCCUAAUAGACUCAAAGCAUAGAGCUGGAGAAAUAACCAGUGAUGGCUUGAGCUUCCUAUUUCUUAAAGAAGUAAAAGUUGCUAAGCCAGAGGAGAUGAAAAACUUAGAGACUCAAGAGGAAGAGUUUUCCGAGCUAGAGGAGCUGGAUGAAGAGGCCUCAGGGAUGGAGGAUGAUGAAGAUACCUCAGGGCUGGAGGAGGAGGAGGAAGAGCCCUCAGGGCUGGAGGAGGAAGAAGAAGAAGAGGCUUCAGGGUUGGAGGAGGAUGAGGCCUCAGGGCUAGAGGAGGAAGAGGAACAGACUUCAGAACAGGACUCAACCUUUCAGGGUCAUACUUUGGUAGAUGCAAAGCAUGAAGUUGAGAUAACCAGUGAUGGCAUGGAAACUACUUUCAUUGACUCUGUAGAGGAUUCUGAAUCAGAGGAGGAAGAAGAAGGAAAGAGCUCUGAAACAGGAAAGGUAAAGACUACCUCCCUGACUGAGAAAAAAGCCUCACGUAGACAAAAAGAAAUUCCCUUUAGUUAUUUGGUUGGGGACUCUGGGAAGAAAAAGUUGGUGAAACACCAGGUGGUGCACAAAACCCAGGAGGAAGAGGAAACAGCUGUGCCCACAAGUCAAGGAACUGGCACACCCUGUCUGACCUUAUGUUUGGCCUCUCCCUCAAAGUCACUAGAGAUGAGUCAUGAUGAGCAUAAAAAGCAUUCACAUACAAAUUUGAGUAUUUCAACAGGAGUCACCAAACUUAAGAAAACAGAAGAAAAGAAACACAGAACUCUGCACACAGAAGAACUAACAUCCAAAGAAGCAGACUUAACAGAGGAAACAGAAGAAAACUUGAGAAGUAGUGUGAUUAAUAGCAUCAGAGAGAUAAAAGAGGAGAUUGGAAAUUUGAAAAGUUCCCAUUCAGGUGUCUUGGAAAUUGAAAAUUCAGUAGAUGAUCUGAGUAGCAGAAUGGACAUACUUGAAGAAAGAAUAGACAGUCUAGAAGAUCAAAUUGAAGAAUUCUCUAAGGAUACAAUGCAAAUGACCAAACAGAUAAUUAGUAAAGAAAGGCAAAGAGAUAUAGAGGAGAGAUCUAGAAGUUGCAACAUUCGUUUGAUAGGAAUUCCAGAAAAGGAGAGUUAUGAGAAUAGGGCAGAGGACAUAAUUAAAGAAAUAAUUGAUGAAAACUUUGCAGAACUAAAGAAAGGUUCAAGUCUUGAGAUUGUCAGUGCUUGUCGAGUACCUAGUAAAAUUGAUGAAAAGAGACUGACUCCUAGACACAUCUUGGUGAAAUUUUGGAAUUCUAGUGAUAAAGAGAAAAUAAUAAGGGCUUCUAGAGAGAGAAGAGAAAUUACCUACCAAGGAACAAGAAUCAGGUUGACAGCAGACUUAUCACUGGACACACUGGAUGCUAGAAGUAAAUGGAGCAAUGUCUUCAAAGUUCUGCUGGAAAAAGGCUUUAAUCCUAGAAUCCUAUAUCCAGCCAAAAUGGCAUUUGAUUUUAGGGGUAAAACAAAGGUAUUUCUUAGUAUUGAAGAAUUUAGAGAUUAUGUUUUGCAUAUGCCCACCUUGAGAGAAUUACUGGGGAAUAAUAUACCUUAGCACGCCAGGGUGACUACAAACAAUAUGCUUUCCUCCCCCAGCAUGCAUCCAAAAAUCAACAAGUAAAACGAAAAUACACUUCUACCCAGAAGGAUGGACAGCUAAUAGCGUACUUGGGGAUGAGGAGCAAGGAAUAUUACAGAUAUUACCUAGAUGUUAAUAAAGGGUAUGUUUAAAAAAAAUAGGCUGGUCUCAAUGUAGUGAGUUAUUUCAGUUGAUCACAGUCAGUUACAGAUAGAAUUCCUUGUUUUACUUCCCCCCCACCACCUCCCUACUGCAGUUGACUAGUCUUUUUAGAAUUUAUAUUAUCUGGCUGGGCACGGUGGCUCACACCUGUAAUCCCAGCACUUUGGGAGGCCGAGGCGGGUGGAUCACGAGGUCAGGAGAUCGAGACCAUCCUGGCUAACACAGUGAAACCCCGUCUCUACUAAAAAUAAAAAAAAUUAGCCGGGCAUGGUGGCGGGCGCCUGUAGUCCCAGCUACUUGGGAGGCUGAGGCAGGAGAAUGGCGUGAACCCAGGAGGCGGAGCUUGCAGUGAGCCGAGAUCACACCACUGCACUCCAGCCGGAGCCACAGAGCGACACUCCGUCUCAAAAAAAAGUAUAUUGUGCUAGCUUGUCUAAGAAUAAACUUCUAUACUGUUGGGGGAGGGCUGCACCUGUCAAGAUAACCUGUCAAUGUAGUAGGAAAACAGGAGGGGACAGUAACAGAAAAGCACGGGAAAAGAUGGCAAGGUUAGUUAAAAUAGAAAAGUGCUCAGUUCCUCAUACCUGUAAUCCCAGCAGUUUAGGGGGCCAAGGCAGGUGGGUCACUUGAGCCCAAGAGUUCAAGGCCAUCCUGGGCAAUGUGGCGAAAGUGUCUACAAAAAAAUACAAAAAGAGGAAGAAAUGAUAUUUCACAAGUUUGUAUCAUUUGUCAUGAUGUGACUCGAAUAUAUUAAAUCUUUUUCCUUUGAA